AACCCGGAAGGUCCGGCGUCCCAGCCGCCUACCUCGCUGGGACCCUGGUCUUGCUGUCCCCCGCUGGCCUCCUGCCCAAGCGACUGCGGCCAGGAUGGGCCGGAAGGUGACCGUGGCCACCUGCGCACUCAACCAGUGGGCCCUGGACUUCGAGGGCAAUUUGCAAAGAAUUUUAAAGAGUAUUGAAAUUGCCAAAAACAGAGGAGCAAGAUACAGGCUUGGACCAGAGCUGGAAAUAUGCGGCUACGGAUGUUGGGAUCAUUAUUACGAGUCGGACACCCUCUUGCACUCGUUUCAAGUCCUAGCGGCCCUUGUGGAGUCUCCCGUCACUCAGGACAUCAUCUGCGACGUGGGGAUGCCUGUAAUGCACCGAAACGUCCGCUACAACUGCAGAGUGAUAUUCCUCAACAGGAAGAUCCUGCUCAUCAGACCCAAGAUGGCCUUGGCCAAUGAAGGCAACUACCGCGAGCUGCGCUGGUUCACCCCGUGGUCGAGGAGUCGGCACACAGAGGAGUACUUUCUGCCUCGGAUGAUACAGGACCUGACAAAGCAGGAAACCGUACCCUUCGGAGAUGCGGUGCUGGUGACAUGGGACACCUGCAUUGGAAGUGAGAUCUGUGAGGAGCUCUGGACACCCCACAGCCCGCACAUCGACAUGGGCCUGGAUGGCGUGGAGAUCAUCACCAACGCCUCGGGCAGCCACCAAGUGCUGCGCAAAGCCAACACCAGGGUGGAUCUCGUGACUAUGGUCACCAGCAAGAACGGUGGGAUUUACUUGCUGGCCAACCAGAAGGGUUGUGACGGGGACCGCCUGUACUACGACGGCUGUGCCAUGAUUGCCAUGAACGGAAGCGUCUUUGCUCAAGGAUCCCAGUUUUCUCUGGAUGACGUGGAAGUCCUGACGGCCACGCUGGAUCUGGAGGACGUCCGGAGCUACAGGGCGGAGAUUUCAUCUCGAAACCUGGCGGCCAGCAGGGCGAGCCCCUACCCCAGAGUGAAGGUGGACUUUGCCCUCUCGUGCCACGAGGACUUGCUGGCACCCAUCUCUGAGCCCAUCGAGUGGAAAUACCACAGCCCUGAGGAGGAGAUAAGCCUUGGACCUGCCUGCUGGCUCUGGGAUUUUUUAAGACGAAGUCAACAGGCAGGGUUUUUGCUGCCCUUGAGUGGCGGGGUGGACAGCGCAGCCACCGCCUGCCUCAUCUACUCCAUGUGCUGCCAGGUCUGCGAGGCCGUGAGGAGUGGAAAUGAGGAAGUGCUGGCUGAUGUCCGCACCAUCGUGAACCAGAUCAGCUACACCCCCCAGGAUCCCCGAGACCUCUGUGGACGCAUACUGACCACCUGCUACAUGGCCAGCAAGAACUCCUCCCAGGAGACGUGCACCCGGGCCAGAGAGUUGGCCCAGCAGAUUGGAAGCCACCACAUCAGUCUCAACAUCGAUCCAGCCGUGAAGGCCGUCAUGGGCAUCUUCAGCCUGGUGACGGGGAAGAGCCCUCUGUUUGCAGCUCAUGGAGGAAGCAGCAGGGAAAACCUGGCGCUGCAAAAUGUGCAGGCUCGAAUACGGAUGGUCCUCGCCUAUCUGUUUGCUCAGUUGAGCCUCUGGUCUCGGGGUGUCCACGGUGGGCUCCUCGUGCUGGGAUCCGCCAACGUGGAUGAGAGUCUCCUGGGCUACCUGACCAAGUACGACUGCUCCAGUGCGGACAUCAACCCCAUAGGCGGGAUCAGCAAGACGGACCUCAGGGCCUUCGUCCAGUUCUGCAUCCAGCGCUUCCAGCUUCCUGCCCUGCAGAGCAUCCUGUUGGCGCCGGCCACCGCAGAGCUGGAGCCCUUGGCUGAUGGACAGGUGUCCCAGACCGACGAGGAAGAUAUGGGGAUGACAUAUGCGGAGCUCUCGGUCUAUGGGAAACUCAGGAAGGUGGCCAAGAUGGGGCCCUACAGCAUGUUCUGCAAACUCCUCGGCAUGUGGAGACACAUCUGCACCCCGAGACAGGUCGCUGACAAAGUGAAGCGGUUUUUCUCCAAGUACUCCAUGAACAGACACAAGAUGACCACGCUCACACCCGCGUACCACGCCGAGAACUACAGCCCUGAGGACAACAGGUUUGAUCUGCGACCAUUUCUGUACAACACAAGCUGGCCUUGGCAGUUUCGGUGCAUAGAAAAUCAGGUGCUACAGCUCGAGAGGGCAGAGCCACAGUCCCUGGACGGCGUGGACUGAGGCCGGUUCCUUCCUGGAGGCCUCCUGUCCUCGGGGACCCCAGCACCUCAUCAUCAGCAUUGCUGGAGCCAAGGGUAGGAGCCCUACACUAGGAGCCCAGGAUGGGACGGCGCAUCAGCCGAGAGGGAGGGAACUUUUCAGUCAAAUUCCUCAAAAAGAGGCUGGAAUAAAGCCUGGGCUUAAAAAGAGGCUGGAAUCCAAUGCACAUGAUUUUGACCUCCCGCCAGCGUGCGCUUCCCCGCGAAGUCUGGCAUUCUCCGAAGGAAGCCGCCUGGGUAGGAGGGUUCCAACCGCCGCCCCGUGUGGCAUCUUUGCUGCAGGAACAAGAACAGUAGCUCCCGGGAAGGGAGGGGUGUCAUGAGCAGAAAAUGAAGGAGAGAAGACCUUCUCUCCCACCCACACACACCUUCCUGUCCUGGGUUCCAGAAGGUUCUGGGGAGAUGGUCCCUGCAGAGCUUUCUUCC